GCGCGUGCGCUCGGCUCCGCCUGGUGCGGCCGCGGCCGGGAGGGACUGGAUUAUGUCGGCCCCGUUUGAGGAGCGGAGUGGGGUGGUACCGUGCGGGACCCCGUGGGGCCAGUGGUACCAGACCUUGGAGGAGGUGUUCAUUGAAGUUCAGGUGCCGCCAGGCACGCGCGCCCAGGAUAUCCAGUGCGGCCUCCAGAGCCGGCAUGUGGCGCUGUCGGUGGGCGGCCGCGAGAUCCUCAAGGUAGCGGCAGCUCGGGGCUUGUGUUCAGUUUCCUCUUCCCAGACGCCCCCAGCCCCGUUUCCCUGAACGACUGUUGGGUGUCCCGACGGCUCCUGUGGCUGGCAGAAAGAGAAAGAGGAUAACACUGACCAGGUUUGGGUCUGGUCAGAGCCCCCGCCUCUUCAGGGCAGGUGCUGAGUUGUGGAAAUUUGAGGAGCCUAUUUUCGUGUUUAGUUUUCAAACUAAGACUGCUGCUUCUGCUUCUCUGACGGGCUUCAGCUGGGAACAGAUUAACUAGGUUGCUAAAGGAACAAAUAUUUCUUCCGUGCACUGAAGACAGGCAGGAAGACAACAGAUAACGUACCUGCAGUGGAGAGGUUAAGCUCCUGUACGGAAGCGUAAUUCAUAAAUAGAUAAAUAUAGGAAAGGACAACAAAGAAAAUAGGGAUAGAAUAACGGGCAGAGAAUUUAGAGAUGAUGUCAGGUGAUUAGUUUUCUCAUCUAAAAGCUUGAAAAUCCUGCAUGUUUGUGGAGUGGUCAAGCAGGUGGUGAAGAGGUGUGUGCAUAAAAUAAGUAGUACUCCUUUUAUUUCUUUUCACCAAUGCUCUUUGGAUCUGGACCCGCUUUUUCUUUGUUAAGUGUAUAAUUAAACUAACAGGUUGAAAUUAGAUUUAGUUCUCAGGUUAGAUGCCCAAGAUGUUUGAUGGCAGUGUAAUAUGGUGAAGGGAGACUACUUGUUUCCUAGUUUUGUAAACUUGGGCGAGAGAUUGUUCAGUGUCUCUAUAUCUUCCUUAUCCACAAGAUAAGGUAGUUAUAGUACCCUUCUCAUGGGAUUGUUUUGAGCUUAACAUGGUAUUCACGUGUAUGAAGAGCUUGGAGUAUUCACUGGGCAAACUCUUUGAUUCUACAAUAGCUGAUGAGGGAACAUGGACUUUGGAGGACAGAAAAAUGGUUCGUAUUGUUCUUACAAAGACAAAGAGAGAUGCAGCAAAUUGUUGGACUUCUCUACUAGAAUCUGAAUAUGCAGCGGAUCCUUGGGUGCAAGACCAAAUGCAGAGAAAGCUUACAUUAGAGAGAUUCCAAAAAGAAAAUCCUGGUUUUGACUUCAGUGGAGCAGAAAUCUCAGGAAACUACACUAAAGGUGGACCAGAUUUCUCAAACCUUGAGAAAUAACUGCUUUUUUUCCUGCAUUCUGUGGAUCCUAGCAGAUAUUGCCAACUUAAUCAGAUAAACAGAUUAUGUAAUGGAAGAAAAAUGCGGAUGCCUACAGUUAACAGAUUGCAAAAUGUAUCUUAAAAUGGUUCUAAAAAUUGCAUUCAAACAUAAUUUACAUAGGAAAUGUACUGUGGGAACUAUUCUAUGGAUAUAUGGUAAAGUUGUUUUGGACUUGUUUUUGCUCAGCAUGAAGUUUUAUAUGCUGCAUUUUACUAAUUCCAUAUUUAACCAUAUUUUUAAUACAAAAGAACAUUAGAGUAUAGAUCAUGUGAAAUGAAGGGUGCCUUUGGGGAAAAUUAACUUUUUCUUUUGAUAAGUAUGAUAUUCAAUAAAAUUUUCUAAAUAGGAAUUGUGUACCCCUUUGUCUAAGUAUAACAAUUCACACAAAAUUAUAGUGCUGAAAACAAUUUUAAUAAAGGAAAAAGUCCAUAAAUGUAUUUUAAGUAAAUUAAGAGUUAAUGUAAAUUUCUUAAUUAGAAUAUUAUUACUUGAGGGAUUACUUUAUGUCAAGAAGUUUAAAAAUAGUUAAAACCCUAACAAUAGAAGUGGAUUAACACAAAAGAGAAGUGUGAUCAUGGUAAUUAGGUGAGUCCUUUGUGGCAGAAAGCAAAGUAAGGUCACUAAUUGUAUAUCAGUGGCAUCAUUUUGAUUGUAAGUGAUUUAGGCAUAUAGGUAGGAAUUGUCUAUAGACAUUUUAUUCAAUAUCCUAUUUAUGUCCUUUUUAUUUUUUGCCCUUUUUAACUCUUGAAAAAAUUUUAAAUCUCAUGCAUAGAAAAGUUACAGAUAAUUUUUUUCUUUCUGAACCAUUUGUGAUUUAGUUGAAGACAUGAUUCCUCAUUACUGAUUACUAUCUGCUUCAAAUUAUCUUACAUGACUACAAUGCAACCAUUAGAAUCAGGAAAUUUACGUUGACACAUUACUACCCUCUAAUCCUCAGAUCUUCACUUCAUUCACAUUGAACUGAUUGUCCCAAUAAUGUCCAUAUAGCAAGAGGAUCCAGUCAGAAUCAUGCCUUUCAUUUAGAUGUCAGCUGUCUUUAGUUUACUUCAUUCUGGAACAAAUUCUCAUUUGUUUCCUUUUACAACUUAGUACUUUUGACAAUUAUGGGCUAGUUUUGUAGAACACCCCUUAUUUUGAGUUCUGUCUGAUACUUCAUGAUUAGAUUGAGGUUAUUCAUCUUUGGCAGGAAUGUGAUAGAAGUGCAUCCUGUCAUUGUUUAAUAAUUUCAGUUUGUCUCAUUUCUGAUGGUGUUUCUUAGAUGACUGAUUAAGGUAGUGUCUGCCAGACUUCUCCACUGUAGUUAUUUUUAUAAUUAUUUCUUGAGAAGAUAGUUGCAAAAUACUACCUUGUUUCUGAUCAGACUUUAAAUUUAUCGUAUCUCUAUAAACUCAUUAUUUUCUAUUUUAUUCAGCAGGUUAAAAAACCUAUUAUCAUUACAUUGGUGCUCAAAAUUAUUGUACAUUUGGCUGGUAGAAGUCCAUUCUGGGUGGCCUCUGUGUCCUUCUGACACAUUCCCAUCAUUAUUCAAUGAAUUUGUUACUCUCUGGCAUAAGAUAUACCAGGCUUCUCAUGCUGUCCUCGACCUAACCCAAGAAUCAGCCAUUUUUCCGUAGAGCCUGGGUUCUCUUUAGUGAGUAAUAUUUAAAAGCCAAGAUCUGUGCUAGUGUGCAAUUGCCGUUGGUGUGUAUAUAUAAUGCAUGUCUUUACAUCUAUAUUUCUGCAUCUAUGUAUAUUGAAAACCAUGAAUUCACAUAUAAAUUCUGAUCCCAUGGGCUUCAUUUUCAUUUUUUCCUUCUCCACAUUUAUAACCGUUUUCAGUACCAGUGAGAAACCUGAUUCCUAUUUGAUUAUUUGUGGGGUUUUUUUUUUUUAAGGUGGAGUUUCACUCUUGUUGCCCAGACUGGAGUGCAGUCGCGCGAUCUCGGCUUACUGCAACCUCCGCCUCCUGGGUUCAAGCGAUUCUCCUGCCUCAGCCUCCCAAGUAGCUGGGAUUACAGGCAUGCGCUGCCACACCUGGCUAAUUUUUAAUUUUUGGUAGAGACGGGGUUUCUCCAUGUUGGUCAGGCUGGUCUCGAACUCCGGACAUCAGGUGAUCCGCCCGCCUGGGCCUCCCAAAUUGCUGGGAUUACAGGUGUGAGCCACUGCGCCUGGCCUGAUUCUCUAUUGUAGGUCAUCUCCCCACAUGAAUGUCUUCCUCACCCUGCUUAGGCUUCGCAUCCUAUGCUGAGCAGGAAUGUCCUCCUCAUCCUGCCUGGACCCUAAUACCUCACUCCAGGCCAUGGCAGUCCAUUCACCCUGUGAUUCCUAUCUUGCUCAUUUUAGGAAUGAAUUGUCGGGGGAAGAGGCUAUUUUUCUUUUAAUUUUAUUCUCUUUGACAUUUAACAAAAUUUUUUGAGUAAAGUAAAAUUAACUUUUUUGGUGUAUGGUUUGGUGAAUUUUAAGUAUAGAUAUGUGUAAACACCUCCACAGUCAGAGUAUUGAAGAGUUCAAUCACCGUAAAAACUCUCGUGCUCUCUUUGUACUCUACACACCCUACUCCCAGCCCCUAAACCUUGGAAACCACUGAUCUAAUCCCCAUCUCCAUAUUUUUGUCUUCAAGCAUGUUAUAAAUGGGAUCAUAUAUAAUUAAGAAAAACGCUUUAUUGUAACAACAUACAUUUCACCCAUUUAAGGUGUGUAAUUCAGUAGCUUUUAGUAUAUACACAGAUAAAUGCAACCAUUCCAAUAAUCAAUUUUAGAAUGUUUUCAUCACCUCAGAUAGAAACCUUGUAUAGUUUAGCUUUUAUCCUUCUCCUGUCAUCCCCCGCCAUCCAUACUACCUCUUUUCAUCUCAUAGAUUUCCUUAUUCUGGACAUUUCAUGUACAUGGAAUCAUAAUACGUGGUCUUUGGUUACUGGCUUCCUUCACUUUACAUGUCUUAAGAGGUUCAUCUAUAUUCGAGCAUGUAUCAGCACAUUCAUUAGUAUGUCUGAAAAUACUUCAUUGUAUGGCUGUAGCACUUUGUUUAUACAUUUGUAAGUUGGACAUUUUGGGUAUUUCCACCCUUUGGCUGUCCUGACUAAAGCUGCUAUAAACGUGUACAAGUCUUUAUGUGCAUAUGUGUUUUCAUUUCUUACCUAGGAGUAGAAUUUUUAGGUUAUAUGAUAACUAUGUUAAUCAUUUGAGGAGCUGUCAUUGUUUCCCAAAGCAGCUACAUCUUUUUACUUUCCCACCAGCAGUGUAUGCAGGUUCCAUUUUCUCUGCAUCCUUGCCAAUACUUGUUUACCUGACAUUUUGAUUUUAGUCACUCUAGUGGAUAUGAAAUGGGAUCUCUAUCUAGUUUUGGUUUGCUAUUCUCUGAUACUAUGUUGAGCAUUCUUUCUUGUGCUUAUUGGCUAUUUGUGUAUCUUCCUUAAAGCAGUGUUUAUUCAAAUUAUUUACCCAUUUUUUUAGUUGUCUUAUUGGGUAGUAAGAGUCUUUAUAUAUUCUGGGUACAAGUCUCUUACCAGGUAUAUGAUUUGUAAUUUCUCCUAUUCUCUCUUUACUUUGUUGAUAGUGUCUUUUGAAGCACAGACUUAAUUUUGAUGAAGUCUUAUCCAUCAUGCCAUUGGUGGAUCAUGUUUUUGGUGUCAUGUCUAGGAACCUUAACCCCAGGUCAUGAGGAAUUUUUCUUUUUUCUUUUUUUGACUCACAUUCUCACUCUGUCACCCAGGCUGGGGUGCAGUGGCACAAUCUCCACUCACUGCAACCUCUGCCUGCUGGGUUCAAGUGAUUCUUGUGCUUCAGUCUCCCAAGUAGCUGGGACUACAGGUGUGCACCACCACUCCCAGCCCAUUUUUUUUUUAUUUUUUAUUUUUAGUAGAGUUGGGAUUUCACCAUAUAGGCUAGGCUGGUCUUGAACUGACCUCAACGGAUCUGCCCGCCUCAGCCUCUGAAGUGCUGGGAUUACAGGCAUGAGCCACCGUGCCCGGCCUAUGGAUUUUUUUCUUCUAAAAAUUUUAUAAAUUUAGUUCUACAUUUAGAUCCGUGAUCCAUUUUAGGUUAAUUUUUGUAUAAGCUGUGAAAUUUAGGUAGGUUUAUUUUUUUGCAUAUGGAUGUUCAGUUGUUUUAAAAUCGUCUGUUGAAAAACUCUCCAUUCCCCAUUGAGUUGUCUUUUCACCUUUGUCAGAAAUCAAUUGCUAUUUAUGUGAGUCUGGUUUUGGACUUUAUUCCAUCGAUCUAUGUGUUUAUCCUUUCAUAAAUACCAGAUUGCCUUGAUUAUCACAGCUUUAUAGUAAGUCUUAAAACUGGGCAGCAUGAUUCCUUCAAAAUUUUUUUGAAAUCUUUUUCAAAAUUGUUUUGGCUAAUUUAGUUUCUUUGCCUUCCAUAUGAAUUUUAGAAUUAGCUACUCUGUAUCUACAAAAAAUCCUACUGGGGUUUUGAAUGCAAUUUUGUGUCUUCCAAUCCAUGAACAUGAGGUAUCUAUUUAGGACCUCUUUCAUUUCAGUUAUCAGCAUUUUAUGUCAUUUUUCAGCAUAUAUUCCACAGUGUUCAUUUUGGAGGAACUAUUGUUAAGUUGUAUUAUUUUUGAAACAUGGGUUUCCAAUUGCACAUCGCUAGUAUGUACAAAUGUGUUUGAUUUUUGUUUGUUGACCUUGUAUCCUGUGACCUUGCUAAACUUCAUUAGUUUUGGGAGUUAUUUUGUUGUUAACUCAUUAAGUUUUCUACAUAAACUACGAAUAGAAACAGUUUUAUUUUAUUCUUUUUAGUCUAUGAUUUUUCUUGCCUGAUUUUGUUGUUAACUCAUUAAGUUUUCUACAUAAACUACGAAUAGGAACAGUUUUAUUUUAUUCUUUUUAGUCUAUGAUUUUUCUUGCCUGAUUGCAGUGGCCAGAACAAUAACAUGGAGAAAGUGGCCAUCUCAGUCUUGUUCUGGAUCUUAGGAUUUUGAAAGCAUUGUUUUUGACCAUUAUGUAUGCAAGCUGUAGGCUUUUCUUAAAUUCCCUUUGUCAUGUUGAGCAAGUUCCCAUCUAUUAAUUUGUUGUUAGCAGAGUUUCAUGAGUGGAUGCUGAAUUUUCUAUGCUCUUUCUGUAUCAGUUUGGUCAUUCUUUUUGUUUAGACUGUUAAAAUCAUGGAUUUUACUGAUUCCAGAAUUUUGAAACAGCUUAUAUUUCCUCCCAACCCCAAACUUGGUCAUGGUACAUUAUUCAGCUUAUGUAUCUAGAUUUUUAUUUUUUGAGGAUUUUUAUGUCUGUGUUCAUUUUGGAUAUUGUGCAAUUGUUUUUGUUUGUUUUUUCCUUGUGUUAUCUUUAUCUUGGUAUGGUAUCAUGUUAAUUCUGGUCUUGUAAAAUGAAUUGCAAAGUGAUUAUUCUUUCUGGAAGAGAUUUGUAGAAUUUGUUAUAUCUUUAAAUGUUUUAUGAAUUUGCUAGUAAGGUUUUAAACAAUGGUUCAAUUUUUAAAAAUAGAGAAUUUAUUGAGGUUUAUUUAAGUUUGGGUACUGUAUGCCUUUCAAGGAAUUGGUUCAUCUAAUCCUAUGUGCAUAGAGUUGUUCAUGGUAUUUUCUUUGUGUCGUUCUAAUGAGGAUCUAUACUGUUAUCUUUUCUUUGAUUCCUAAGAUUGGAAUCAAAGAUUGGAAUUCCUUCUCUUUUUUUGUCAAUUUUGCCAGAGGUUUAUCAAUUUUACUGCUCUUUUCAAAAAUUAGUUUUUUGAUUGUUUUCUAUUAAUUUGUUUACAAUUGCAUUUAUUUUCUGCCUCUUUUUUUUUUUUCUUCUUUCUGCUUGCUUUAGGUUUAGUUUGGGCUUCUUUUUUUUGUAGACAGGUCUCACUUCAUCACCCAGACUGGAGUAGUGUUAUGAUCAUAGCUCACUGCAGCCUCAAACUCGUGGGGUCAUGAUCCUCCUACCUCAGCCUUCUGAGUGGCUGGGACUAUAGUGGUGUGCCACCACACCCAGUUAGAUUUUCCUACUUUCUUAAAGUGGGAGCUUAGAGUGUUAAUUUGAGAACUUUUUCUUGUUUAGUAAAAAGCAGUCGAUUGUUAUAAAUUGCAGCACCAGCAUGGCUGCAUUCCAAGCACGGUGAUAUUUUCAUUUAUUUUAAAAUAUUUUUUAAGACUUCCCUGUAGUAUCAUGAGUUAUUUAGAAAUGUGUUGUUUAAUUUCCAAGUGUUUGGAGAUUUUCUUGCUGUUACUGAUUUCUAGAUUAUGGUCAAAAAACAUAUUUUAUAUGAUUUCAUCUCUUUUAAAUUUGUUAAGGUUUAAGACCCAUGAUGUGGUUUAUCUUGGUGAGUGUUCCAUGUGUACUUGAAAAGAAUGCUUAUUCUGCUGUUUUAGGUAGAAGGGUUUUAUGUCAAUUAAAUCUAGCUGGUUAUUAGUAUUAUUCCAUUUUCCUACAUCUUUGCUAAUUUUCUAUUAAUUCUAUGGACUACUGAGAGAGGAAUGUUUAAGUUUCCAACUGUAAAUGAAGAUUUGUCCAGUCCUCCUUUUAAUGCUACCACUUUUUGCUUCAUGUUUUUUUUUUUUUUUUUGAGUCUUACCCUGUCACUCAGGCUGGAGCAUAGCAACUCUGUCAUGCUUCACUGCAGCCUCAAACUCCUGGGCUCAGACAGUCUUCCCACCUCAGGCUCCUCAGUACCUAGGACUACAGAUGUAUAUCACUAUGCCUAGCUAAUUUUUGAUUUUUUGUAGAGAUAGGGUCUCCCUAUGUUGAGUAGGCUGGUCUUGAACUCUUGGCCUCAAGCAAUCCUCCCACCUUGGCUUCCCAAAGCAUUGGAAUUACAGGAAUGAAUGAGUCUCUGUACCUGGUCUCUUCAUGUAUUUUUAAGAUCUGAUAAUAAGUGCUUACACUUUUAGCACUGUCUUGGUGAAUUUUAUCAUUAUAUAAUGUCCCUAAUUAUCCUUGGCAAUUUUGGUUGUUCCUAACUCUACUUUGAUGAAUAUAAAAAUGGCUUUUUAAUUUAUUUUUUGAGACAAGAGCCUCACUCUGUUGCCCAGGUUGGAGAGCAGUGGUGUGAUCUUGUCUCACUGCCUCACAGGUUCAAGCAAUUCUCCUGCCUCAGUCUCUGGAGUAACUGGUACUACAGGCAUGCGCCACCACACCCAGCUGAUUUUUGUAUUUUUAGUAGAGAUGGGGUUUCACCAUGUUGGCCAUGCUGGUCUCGAACUCCUGGCCUCAAGUGAUCCGUCCACCUUGGCCUCCCAAAGUGCUGGGAUUACAGGUGUGAGCCACUGCGCUCGGCCUUAAAAAUUGGCUUAUCUUUUAAUUCAUCUUGACUCAUGUUUACUGUUUUUUGGUUUCUGAAAAAUAGAUUUAAUAAAUAAUAACAUUUUAUCAAAGUUAUUAGUAUAGAGAAAUAAAUUGAGUGUUGUUAUUAUUCUAUGAUCAUGAUGACAGCACAGAAGUUAAUGUGGCCAGCAUAUAGUUUUGAUUAAAAAUUAUACAAGCAA